AUGUUUCUGACAGAGAGAAAUACGACAUCUGAGGCCACAUUCACUCUCUUGGGCUUCUCAGAUUACCUGGAACUGCAAAUUCCCCUCUUCUUUGUAUUUCUGGCAGUCUACGGCUUCAGUGUGGUAGGGAAUCUUGGGAUGAUAGUGAUCAUCAAAAUUAACCCAAAAUUGCAUACCCCCAUGUAUUUUUUCCUCAACCACCUCUCCUUUGUGGAUUUCUGCUAUUCCUCCAUCAUUGCUCCCAUGAUGCUGGUGAACCUGGUUGUAGAAGAUAGAACCAUUUCAUUCUCAGGAUGUUUGGUGCAAUUCUUUUUCUUUUGCACCUUUGUAGUGACUGAAUUAAUUCUAUUUGCGGUGAUGGCCUAUGACCACUUUGUGGCCAUUUGCAAUCCUCUGCUCUACACAGUUGCCAUCUCCCAGAAACUCUGUGCCAUGCUGGUGGUUGUAUUGUAUGCAUGGGGAGUCGCAUGUUCCCUGACACUCGCGUGCUCUGCUUUAAAGUUAUCUUUUCAUGGUUUCAACACAAUCAAUCAUUUCUUCUGUGAGUUAUCCUCCCUGAUAUCACUCUCUUACCCUGACUCUUAUCUCAGCCAGUUGCUUCUUUUCACUGUUGCCACUUUUAAUGAGAUAAGCACACUACUCAUCAUUCUGACAUCUUAUGCAUUCAUCAUUGUCACCACCUUGAAGAUGCCUUCAGCCAGUGGGCACCGCAAAGUCUUCUCCACCUGUGCCUCCCACCUGACUGCCAUCACCAUCUUCCAUGGCACCAUCCUCUUCCUCUACUGUGUACCCAACUCCAAAAACUCCAGGCACACAGUCAAAGUGGCCUCUGUGUUUUACACCGUGGUGAUCCCCUUGUUGAAUCCCCUGAUCUACAGUCUGAGAAAUAAAGAUGUUAAGGAUGCAAUCCGAAAAAUAAUCAAUACAAAAUAUUUUCAUAUUAAACAUAGGCAUUGGUAUCCAUUUAAUUUUGUUAUUGAACAAUAA